GCAUCCCUGCCCGGAGCGCAGCCGGCGCGGGCGCGGGACCGAGGCGAACCGGGUGCGGAGCCAAUACCCGCGGCAGCAGCACCAGCCUAGGCCGAUUCUCCUGAGCUCACAGGCACAUUCCACUCUCCAUCCUAGGCUGAUGAUUAACUACUGACCCUCCCAGGCGAUGCGUCCGUGGGAAAAACAAGACCAGCUGUGGUCCAUCUCUGCCAACACCCCAAAAUUUUAUGCAAUGAGCAUGUUCUUUAAUAAUUAGUGGACUACCUGGCUUCGAGUUCUGAGAGCAGGGAGGAGGGUGCCUGAUUGAAAAAAAGCUCCUGCCCUCCACUGACUCCAGAGAGGGAGAUCCCCAGUACUUGACUCCAUCACGCAGAUGGGAGCAGGCACCAGCUAUGGAGAGGGAUACAGCUGCGUCUCCACAUGACCCAUCCUGCAUGACACCAAAGCCACCGCCAGACAGUGCCUCGGAUUCUAUGCAAAACCUGGGAAGCGGAGACCUACCCCAGCCCCGGGAGGAAGCUAGCUCUUCAGGGGACCGUCUGAGGACUGGAGUUUGAUCCAUGAACCUGGCUUCGAGGCCUUGCUUUUCUCUCUUCUUCAUUCAUAUUCAUUCCCAACACCUUAGAAGGUGUUGCUUAAUUUAUUUCUAGAAAAGCAGCCCAGAGUCAGUCAUUGAAGCCUUCCCCACCCCCUGGCCAAAAAAAAAAAAAAAAAAAAACUGGACACAUUUUGGAUCUGUUGGGAGCUUGGAGUCCAGUGGUUGGCAUAGUUGUCACAUUGGGAGCAGAGAAGAAGCAACCAGGGGCCCUGAUCAGGGGACUGAGCCGUAGAGUCCCAGGAUGGCACCCAAUGGCACAGCCUCUUCCUUUUGCCUGGACUCUACCGCAUGCAAGAUCACCAUCACCGUGGUCCUUGCGGUCCUCAUCCUCAUCACCGUUGCUGGCAAUGUGGUCGUCUGUCUGGCCGUGGGCUUGAACCGCCGGCUCCGCAACCUGACCAAUUGUUUCAUCGUGUCCUUGGCUAUCACUGACCUGCUCCUCGGCCUCCUGGUGCUGCCCUUCUCUGCCAUCUACCAGCUGUCCUGCAAGUGGAGCUUUGGCAAGGUCUUCUGCAAUAUCUACACCAGCCUGGAUGUGAUGCUCUGCACAGCCUCCAUUCUUAACCUCUUCAUGAUCAGCCUCGACCGGUACUGCGCUGUCAUGGACCCACUGCGGUACCCUGUGCUGGUCACCCCAGUUCGGGUCGCCAUCUCUCUGGUCUUAAUUUGGGUCAUCUCCAUUACCCUGUCCUUUCUGUCUAUCCACCUGGGGUGGAACAGCAGGAACGAGACCAGCAAGGGCAAUCAUACCACCUCUAAGUGCAAAGUCCAGGUCAAUGAAGUGUACGGGCUGGUGGAUGGGCUGGUCACCUUCUACCUCCCGCUACUGAUCAUGUGCAUCACCUACUACCGCAUCUUCAAGGUCGCCCGGGAUCAGGCCAAGAGGAUCAAUCACAUUAGCUCCUGGAAGGCAGCCACCAUCAGGGAGCACAAAGCCACAGUGACACUGGCCGCCGUCAUGGGGGCCUUCAUCAUCUGCUGGUUUCCCUACUUCACCGCGUUUGUGUACCGUGGGCUGAGAGGGGAUGAUGCCAUCAAUGAGGUGUUAGAAGCCAUCGUUCUGUGGCUGGGCUAUGCCAACUCAGCCCUGAACCCCAUCCUGUAUGCUGCGCUGAACAGAGACUUCCGCACCGGGUACCAACAGCUCUUCUGCUGCAGGCUGGCCAACCGCAACUCCCACAAAACUUCUCUGAGGUCCAACGCCUCUCAGCUGUCCAGGACCCAAAGCCGAGAACCCAGGCAACAGGAAGAGAAACCCCUGAAGCUCCAGGUGUGGAGUGGGACAGAAGUCACGGCCCCCCAGGGAGCCACAGACAGGAAGCCAGCACUGUCCUGCACUACGUGCUCCAGCAACCUCCUGAGCUGCUGCAAGAGCCUGUGGGGGCUCAGGUUCCUUCAGAGACACAUGGGAGGCCCCUCGGAGGAGCUAUCGGGGGAGCCACUGUCUGAGGAGCCACAGAAGAGACCUCCCCAGAAAGCGGUGAGGACGCUGCCCUCUGAGGCUGUCUAGACCUAGCCCCAGGACACUGAAGAUACCGCUCCCGGUCCCCAAGAUGUGACUCCUGGAGCUCCUAAGGACCCAGUCUCCAAAGCCACCAAGGACUCACCCUGGACUGAAUCUGGGGGCUCCCAGAACACACAGCUGGGUGUGGGGUCCUCAGGCCUAGGGCGGAACAGCCUAUUCUGUGCUCAGCAUUCCCAGACAGGCACGCAAGACUCCUCUGGGCCCGAGUGGGCUGAAUCCCAUGGGUUCAAAGCUCACGUUGGUGCUGGCCCUGGGAGUCAUGAGCAGAGACGGUGGGACAGACGGGGAUGCGUGCACAUGUGUGUGCAUGGGUGCAUACGUGUAGGGACGUGCAUGACCUCUGAGCAAGGCAGAGGGUAUUGAAGAAAGCAUUGGCCUCUCACUCCCUCAUGGGUUCUGCAGGAUGAAGGAAAGGAAAGGAAAAGACAGAGAAAGGAAGGAAAUAGCUUUUCAUGAGCACCUACUGUGUACCAGGUGCUUCCCUGGCAUGAGCUCUCGUAACCCUUAUAGCAACAUGAGUUUAGAGCAAGAAUCACACCCCGACUUUACAGAGAUGGAAACUGAGGCUCAGAGAAGUAAGGGACCUGCCCAAGGCCACUCAGCACCUAGAAAGUGUGCCUAGCACAUAGGAGGCACACAAAAAUAUGUGUUGAAUGGGUGAAUGAAUGAGAGAACGGGUGAAAAGCCAGGCCUCAAGCCCACACUACUGACACUGCACUACACCACCUCUCAGGAGAGAAGGCAAAUAUUUCCUUGACUCAGCCACCUUCCUCCUAGCAAGGCUUAGACCCCCAGGCUCUGGGGGUCCCUUCCUGCUACAGUAUGACCCUCUCUGGUGCUUGUCAUCAAGAAGUGGUAUGCGGUGGACUUGCUGGAGAGAGUGUCUGCAGCCAGGCAUCAUGGAGGGAGGGAUGGAUCUUGAGGGACUGUAAUGGUUGUGAAUGGGGGAGUUGGCCCCCAGCACUCUCUGGUGGCCGUAUGACCUUGGGCACGUCUCCUGACCACUCUAAGCAGCUUUUGAUUCCCCUGUCCAAGAGGGUAGGCCCCCUGUUCCUAUUUACAGGAUCCAUAAAGAGACUCAAAGAGAUAGGGUAGUGCCAGCCCCAGAGAGAGGGGGCUGUGGAGGGACUUCUACCCCCAGGGCUUCUCAGUGGCAUCUCCUGGCUGGCCCCUGACACUCAAUCUUCCUUGGUUUCCAAGAUGCUUCAUGAUCUUCCCCCUCCCUGACAUCCCCGACCUCCCUUUUCUGUCCCUUUUGCAACUCAUUGUCCUCUACCUGCCAUCAGAUGUGGCUGUUCCUCAGUCUCAGUCCAGAGUCCUCUCUUCUCACUCAGCAUCUCUCCUCCUGUGACCUCGUCUGCACCCACAACUCCAGUUACAAGGCACGAGGUUUGGUUAUGAAAUCACUCACAGAUUUAUAACUGCAGGCUUGGCUCCUUCCGGGAGCUUGAGACCCACUGCCGCCUCCGCAACACCUCCACCUGGGAGUUUCAGAGGCGCUCUCCCUCAGCGUGUCUGCAGCUGCGUGCCUGCAGCUGCGUGCCUGCCUUCUCCCUGCACCUGCUCUGCUCCCCAGGUCCCUUUCUCAGACCAAAGCCUGCCCGGGCUUCACAGGCUGAGGGUCCACCUUGCCACCUCCGUUUGCCUCAGUCCUCAUGGAGCCCUGGCUCCACUGUCUGCUGGCUUCUCCCCAUCUACUCUGUGUCACUCCAUCCGACCACCAUUGUCUCCAUCAGGACAGUUGGAACACCUCUUCUCAGCACUCUCGCCCCCACCCAGUCCACCCCCUACCUGACAGCCAGAGUGGGCCAUGCCAGAUGCAACCCAGGUCAUGCCACACAGGUAGAUAAAACCAUCUUCAGCCCAGCCCUCAGGCCCUGUGUGCUGGGACCCUGCUGGGCCCUCUCCAGCCUCCCCCUGCGCCAGGCCUCCUCCGUCACUUCACUCUGGCCCUGCUGUUCUUUUCCUUUUAGUUUGAUUAACUCACUCUGCCCAUUCCAUGCUCAAAGCUGUUUCCGUGAGGAAAGGCUCCUCCUGCUCAUUUUAGUGCCCUGAAAUGUCACUUCCUUGAGGAAGUCUUCCUUGACCCUCCACACCAAACCAGGCCCCCUGCCACACCCCUCAGAGCUCUCCUUGGAAGGCACUGGCAUGGCUGUUUGCGUGAUUCCUUGAACGUUGUCUGUCUCUCCUCCUCACCAGGCUGUGGGUCCUGUCUGUUUCUGGUGACCGUUGUCUGUCUAACCCCUAGAGGAGAGUUUGUCACAUGGUAGGAGCUUAAUAAAUAUGUGUUGGAUGAAUGAUCAGAGAAAAGAGAGUGCAGAGAGUGGCCAAAACAGAUGCUUUCAGCAGUGUAUCUGCCAAUAAACCUAAAGGCAUGAUUUGCCCUGGUGAUCCCCCCAGAGGUGCUUAGUCUCUUGGCUGAAUUCCUUCUGGAAUCCCCAGAAUCCCCCUCCUUGGAAGUUUUCCCAGGAGUCUGAGGCAGGCAGGUCUCUCAGUCACGGCCACAUGACCUCAAGUGAAAACAAACCAGUCUGGCUGUUCACAGACUCAGCUGGUCAGAGCUCUGGCCCGAGGGGCCCACGCACCACCCGCCACUGCAGAAGACGCCUCCACGUCUGUCUCUGGGCUGCCUCCACCUUCUGCAGGCCUCCUGGAGCCUCUGCUGGCUGCAGAAGUGGGGUGCAUGCUGCCUGGAGGAGGAACAUCUGUGGUGGGACCCCAAAUCCAUGUUUGUGUUACCAUCGUGUUCCAAUAAAACUAUCGAAACAGA